CUCUCUGCCGCGCGCGCAGGUACGGGGCAGAAGUCGCAGAGCCAAGGCACUGAUGUUUGAACUGGAAACUUCAAAACGUUUAAUAAGAGUCUUCAGGAUGGGUUUGAACUAGACAAGCUAGAAAUUUCUUUAGAACACCAGCUCUAGCAUGCAUCUCCCACUUUUGGCUUUCCUGGAGAGGAGCUUGAAGAGGUGGUUCUGCAGACAGCCACAGUGAUACUUAGGAAACCAGAGGAAUGGAUUUGACUUUUCUGCUAGGAUUCUCUGUUAUAGUUUCUCCCUGAGUUGUAAGAGGCAUGGAAAUAUACAUGAAACUGAAGAACCUGCAAGGAAGGGAAGUGGAACUUUCCAUGCUGAGUGAAAACUAACCAAGUGGCAGUUGUGACUGAAAACACUGAAACCUACCACGUCCAGAUUCACUGGAUUGGGGGAUAGAGGAACGGUCACAGCUAGGGAGAAAGAAGUGAUACCGGAAAAGAAAACCUAAAUGAAGAGAAUGAGGAUGACUGCACAGUAGAUGGCCACCUCUACCUCCACAGAGGCAAAGUCAGCCUCGUGGUGGAAUUAUUUUUUUCUUUAUGAUGGUUCCAAGGUAAAGGAAGAAGGCGAUCCAACAAGAGCUGGCAUUUGUUACUUUUAUCCUUCCCAGACCCUGCUAGACCAACAGGAGUUGCUUUGUGGACAGAUUGCUGGAGUUGUCCGCUGUGUUUCUGACAUUUCUGACUCUCCUCCUACUCUUGUUCGUCUGAGAAAACUGAAGUUUGCCAUAAAAGUUGAUGGAGAUUACCUUUGGGUGCUGGGCUGUGCUGUGGAGCUCCCUGAUGUCAGCUGCAAGCGGUUUCUGGAUCAGCUAGUUGGAUUCUUUAAUUUUUACAAUGGACCUGUUUCCCUAGCUUAUGAGAACUGUUCUCAGGAAGAACUGAGCACGGAGUGGGACACCUUCAUCGAGCAAAUUCUGAAAAACACCAGUGAUCUGCAUAAGAUUUUCAAUUCCCUCUGGAACUUGGACCAAACUAAAGUGGAGCCCCUGUUGUUGCUGAAGGCAGCCCGCAUUCUGCAGACCUGCCAGCGCUCGCCUCACAUUCUCGCUGGCUGCAUCCUCUAUAAAGGACUGAUUGUCAGCACCCAACUCCCGCCCUCCCUCACCGCCAAGGUCCUGCUUCACCGAACAGCACCUCAGGAGCAGAGACUCCCUACGGGAGAGGAUGCCCCGCAGGAACAUGGAGCGGCAUUGCCCCCGAAUGUCCAGAUUAUCCCUGUUUUUGUGACCAAAGAGGAAGCCAUUAGUCUCCACGAGUUCCCGGUGGAACAGAUGACAAGGUCUCUAGCAUCUCCAGCAGGACUCCAGGAUGGUUCAGCCCAGCACCAUCCAAAGGGUGGGAGCACAUCUGCCCUGAAAGAAAACGCCACUGGCCAUGUGGAAUCCAUGGCCUGGACCACCCCAGAUCCCACAUCCCCUGACGAAGCUUGUCCAGAUGGCAGGAAGGAGAACGGAUGCUUGUCUGGCCAUGAUCUGGAGAGCAUCAGGCCCGCAGGACUGCACAACUCUGCCAGGGGUGAGGUUCUUGGCCUCAGCUCCUCCCUGGGGAAGGAACUAGUCUUUCUCCAAGAAGAACUCGACUUGUCUGAAAUCCACAUUCCAGAGGCUCAGGAAGUGGAAAUGGCCUCAGGUCAUUUUGCCUUCCUACAUGUGCCUGUUCCAGAUGGCAGGGCUCCUUACUGCAAGGCAUCUCUCAGCGCCUCCAGCAGCCUGGAACCCACGCCUCCUGAGGACACAGCCAUCAGCAGCUUGCGCCCUCCCUCUGCUCCUGAGAUGCUGACCCAGCAUGGAGCCCAAGAGCAGCUCGAAGACCAUCCUGGCCAUAGCAGCCAAGCCCCCAUUCCCAGAGCAGACCCUCUCCCCAGAAGGACCCGCAGGCCCUUGUUAUUGCCUCGCUUAGAUCCAGGACAGAGAGGAAACAAGCUUCCCACGGGGGAACAAGGCCUGGAUGAGGAUGUUGAUGGGGUCUGUGAAAGCCACGCAGCCCCUGGUCUGGAAUGCAGUUCAGGCUCAGCAAACUGUCAGGGUGCUGGCCCCUCUGCAGAUGGAAUCAGCUCCAGGCUGACACCAGCAGAGUCCUGCAUGGGGCUCGUGAGGAUGAAUCUCUACACUCACUGCGUCAAAGGGCUGGUGCUGUCCCUGCUGGCUGAGGAGCCGCUGCUGGGAGACAGCGCAGCCAUAGAGGAAGUGUACCACAGCAGCCUGGCUUCACUGAAUGGGCUGGAAGUCCACCUGAAAGAGACGCUGCCCAGGGAUGAGGCAGCCUCCACGAGCAGCACCUACAACUUCACACAUUACGACCGCAUUCAGAGCUUGCUGAUGGCAAACCUGCCGCAGGUGGCCACCCCGCAGGAUCGCCGCUUCCUCCAGGCCGUCAGCCUGAUGCAUAGCGAAUUUGCCCAGCUGCCCGCGCUUUAUGAAAUGACUGUCAGGCUUCCUGUCACUUCGUGUCACAUCCCACUCCUGUCCUUCACUCCCUCUCAGUCUAUCCAGCCACCCCCAGUGUGGAGAGCAGACUAGACUCCUUUCUCGGACACUGCCAUUGCCUCGUCAUAGAGGCAGGGCAGCCCCAGCUACUCACUCUGAGCCUCAGGGUCCUUGUCUGUGAAAUGGGACCAUACCACCACUGCAGAGCUUAUGUGAGGGGCAAAGCAGAGACUGUAUGCAGAGCACAUUGCAUAGCUGCCAGUAUGUCAAAAAAGCCAGCACUCCACAGUUCCUUUAUGCAAUACUUAUAACUCCAGGAUCUGUGGCUGCUGCCACUGUGGAUGGUCCCGCCACGGACUCUUCCAGCAUCUAGUGAGCUGAAAGGAAGGAAAGAUGGUAUUGGCACUGAAGCCUGAAACUCAGCUGAAGAAAUAGAAUUCCGUGCCAUGACAGCUGCACAUGCCACAUUGGGUGUCCUGGGUCCUCUGUGACAAGAACCUUACUGAGGUCUCUGUGUGGUCUGAGAUUAGCACCAGCAGCAUUGGACCGUUGCCUUCUUUCUUCCUCCAACAGAAAUGCCUCCACGGCUGUGUACGCCUGUUGCAACCCCAUCCAGGAGACAUAUUUCCAGCAGCUGGCACCUGCAGCACGGAGCUCCGGCUUCCCAAACCCUCAGGAUGGCGCCUUCAGCCUCUCCGGCAAAGCAAAGCAGAAGCUGCUGAAGCACGGGGUGAACUUGCUCUGAACUGCACCCAGGAGGUGACUGGGAAGGAGAAAACCAGCAAAGGAAGCUCUGCCUUUUAUAAUUGAAAAGGCCCCUCUAUUUUAUUUUUCUUGAAAACAUUCCCUUUUUUAGGAACCAAAUGAUAUUUGAGUUUUUGUUAUUCCUUUUGCAGAUUGGGAUGUGUUUUGGGGGCAGGGGUUAGUUCUUCAGGUCGGCAGACCCAGAGCACUUGAUAAAGAACUGUAUUUAAUCGGUAGUGUUGGGGCCGGGACGGGCUUGGCUCCCUCUCUGCCAUACUGAGCCUGAGGUAUUUCAUAUCUCCUGCUGUUCCAUCCCAGCUUGAAUUGGUGCCACAAGCUUCCAAGUUGGCAUUUUUUCUAGAACCUGAUCGUCCACUAGCCCAGAGUGUGUGUGUUCAACCCCCACACCAGGUGGUGGUAGGCGGUGUGACUGCACAGCGAGGUGCCGGAUCUGUGAGCAGGCCGACUCCACUCCCACGCCGCAGGUAGGUUUCUCCAGUGCGCUCUUGCUGGGAGGUCCGGAUCGUUCCUGCAGGGAAGCGGCAGCACACGGAGACCACUUGGUUGAAUUCUGUUGGAACUCUACUCAAAUCUAGGGGCGUCUUCUUUGGACCCACAAUGGGGGCAAGCCUUAAUAAUAUGGAAGGGAGUUUGGGCUUUAGAGAUCCCUUUAUAAAAGCUCUGGGGGCUGAGCCCUGAGAAUUCAGUGACAACAGGACCAACCUGCGCUGCCUUUGACUACAAGUGGGCCGUGCAGCUGGUUCCUCUCGAGCGAGUGUCCCUAAAUAGGAGUUUACAAGAUGUCUGGGGGUAAAAGCACUGUGCUUUUCAGUGGUGGCUGCGUGAAAGGGAGCGACACUCAGCUGUGUGUUCCUGGGCUUGUGUGGUACUUAGAACCUCAGUUCUAUUACGUUAUAGUCAGACAUUUUUUUGACAGUAUGAGACAGACUGCAGGAUGAAAAUAUUUGUCAAAAUCUUAACUGAAUGUUUACUGGAAGUACUUGAGAUUCCAUUUGAGAGUUGUAUUGUUAAUAAUUUCAUGUCAGUGAACUGAUAUCUGAUGUUUAUGAUAUGGUGUCUUUUUCUUGAAACAAGCUUCCAAGGGCUAGAAAUAAAAUAGCCAAAAAAUGCUGGAGUUCUGAGUAAUUAAAUGGCAGCAUUUUUUUGUGACAAAGGUAAGGGUUAAGACAGUGUGUGUGUGUGUGUGUGUGUGUGUGUGUGUGUGUGUGCGCGCGCGCGCGCGCGCGUAACGUGGGCGCAUCCCUCUUUUCCUUCCCUGGGUUCAGUGUGGCUGGGUAAGGACCGUCUGUUUGUAGGGCUGCCAGGCUGCAGCCUGCUGCUCCAGGGAGCACCAGCUGCAGCUGAUCCAAUACACCAAGCCUGUGUCUCCCUCUUCUAUCACCUCUCUCCAGGAUCUCUGCUGUCUCUUGGAUCCCAUCUGCCUAGAUGGAAGAGGAUCCUAUCCGAAGCUAGGAUAAAUGUUGUCUUACUCCUCUGCUAUGUUCUCCCAGAAAAAAUUGAUUACAAGUUCUCUGCUGUGGUUGCUGCAGCUCCAGGAAGUCCCCGCAAUGUCUCACGUUGUCUUUGACCAGUGGUCCCCAGUACCAGGCCAGCGAAGACAACUUUAUAAUGUCAUUUGUGUUGUGAAAAUUCUUCCACUGACCCAAAAUGGAACCGUACAAAGCCUAUCCGUGUAUAUGGAAAAGUCUCAUGCACCUGGAUUAACUCAGAAAAAGUAAAGUCCUGAAACUUCACUUUGCAGGUGUGCCCCUUUCUUUCCUCCUUUGAUCCUGCUUAGUUUCUGCAGUGGAGGUUCUGCUCAGAGCCCCAGGGCACUGGCAGCUGCAGCCGUCAUCUCUAAAGCUUGGUAACUGUGGCCCAGAGGCUGCAGAGAAGAAACACUUAACCCGCUGUUUUCCCGUUUUUUAAUAUUUCAGAGGUUUCAGGGGGUCACUCAGGACACGGUUAAUCCCACAGCCCCAGGCCCAUCCCCUCAAAAUUAGCGCCCCCAGAGUACGGGCCAAGCGACGGACAGCCAAGCAGCAUGUUCUUGCUGGAAUGGGCACCACAACCUCUUAUGGCCAUGUUUCCCAAGGGAAGGCAGUGUGCAGGACAGCCUGCCCACCCUGGACUCCUAGUUGACACCGAGUGCCACUGUCAGUGAUCCAGGACCACAGAUUCUAGUGACUCUUCAGGGCAGAAAAGCCUCUGUUUUGGCUUCCUCUGUGCCAGCCAUCUGCCACCUGUGAACUGUAAGGAUAAAGGUCGCAUGAGUGAUUAAUAGUGGUGUGUUAGUCCGUUCUCACGGUUCUAAUAAAGACAUACCCGAGACUGGGUACUUUAUAAAGGAAA